GGCUAGCAUGCUAAUUAACUAUGCAUAACCACGUUUCCUUUCACCAUGUUGAACCCUGACAUAAUUUUUUUUUCCACAAACACCUCACUCUGGAGAAGGAAAUGAUUUUUUUUAAUUAAAAUAAACAUACAUUGGAAAUACUUAGUGCUAAAAUAAGCCUGAAGGAAAGGUUGGAAGUAUGAUGAGUCAGAAAACUGACUGUAAAGAAACCAAUUACUUAACAUAAAACACCAUUAAAGAUAAGCCACGAAAUGUAAGGUCUGCUGGGUAGGAAAGUGGCAAAUGCAAUGAAGCAUGUCUUUAGAUCAUGCAGGUCUAUAACCAACGGUGAAUCUAGCAAAAGUUAUUUUCUCUUUUGGGGAGAAACUUCUUCUUAUUAAAAAAAUAAAAAAUGUUUCAACUUCUUGAGCACCAAGGUCAAUUAUUCUAAAUCUUAAAACCACAGUUUUAAUUUUGCUUUUUUGUUGGUUUUUGUACUUUGGAGUAUUUGUCUACAUUAUCCUUUUUAUAUUUGCCAUAUUUAAAGUCCAAACUAAAAGCAAAUUAUUUUCUCUCCUCAAGUUAAAUGGCUCUAUCUUUUUCUUUAAAAUCCAUUAAGAAAGUGAAACUCCCAAAGUAAGUCCAAAAAAAAGCCCCCAAGUCUGAAAAUGUGGAGCUUUUCUGGCAGUAAUGCAGCUUCUGCAAGUAUUGCAGACCAGAUCAGGUAUCAGAAUUUUAAAGCUUCAGUAACAAAGCUGUCCUAUUGACCCUGAGGAGAUUUAUGAAAUCACUUUCCUGAUGUUAUUGAAACCAAAACACUUUCCUGGACACUGAAUUCAGUCCUAAACAAAGGGCCUCCAACCAACAGCUGUCUUGGGCUGAAUGAGUUAGACUCAACCUCGUGUGACGGAAAAACAGUAAACACAAGCUAACAUUUAAAAGGAAUUGAUGGCACCGUGUAAAUCAGAAGCCCAAGGAGGGCCUGGCUUCAGGUGUGGGGUUCUCUCUCACGCUCUCAAAUCCACAUCCUCCGGAUUAGGUCCAUUUUCAGACAAGCUCCUCCAGCAACUACAUACCAUGCGUCUUCUCAGGUGUGGGUCCUGCAGGAAAACUAAUACACUCUUUGUCCAUAAGUCUCAAAAUAAACUCUCACUGGCUCUGGUUGGAACAUGAGAGCAUCCUUGCCAUUCACCAUGGCCCCGGUCACUAAACGUCUUCACGCCCUGGACUGGUAAUACAGCCUAUCCCAAAGCACCUGGACUGAGAACGGGAAAUGAGUGGUUCCCAGAGUGAAACUGAGGUACUAUUACUAAAUUAAGAUACACCAAGAUGAAGACUGCCACCAACAUCUACAUUUUCAACCUUGCUCUGGCAGAUGCCUUAGCCACCAGUACCCUGCCCUUCCAGAGUGUGAAUUACCUAAUGGGAACAUGGCCAUUUGGAACCAUCCUUUGCAAGAUAGUGAUCUCCAUAGAUUACUAUAACAUGUUCACCAGCAUAUUCACCCUCUGCACCAUGAGUGUUGAUCGAUACAUUGCAGUCUGCCACCCUGUCAAGGCCUUAGAUUUCCGUACUCCCCGAAAUGCCAAAAUUAUCAAUGUCUGCAACUGGAUCCUCUCUUCAGCCAUUGGUCUUCCUGUAAUGUUCAUGGCUACAACAAAAUACAGGCAAGGUUCCAUAGAUUGUACACUAACAUUCUCUCAUCCAACCUGGUACUGGGAAAACCUGCUGAAGAUCUGUGUUUUCAUCUUCGCCUUCAUUAUGCCAGUGCUCAUCAUUACCGUGUGCUAUGGACUGAUGAUCUUGCGCCUCAAGAGUGUCCGCAUGCUCUCUGGCUCCAAAGAAAAGGACAGGAAUCUUCGAAGGAUCACCAGGAUGGUGCUGGUGGUGGUGGCUGUGUUCAUCGUCUGCUGGACUCCCAUUCACAUUUACGUCAUCAUUAAAGCCUUGGUUACAAUCCCAGAAACUACGUUCCAGACUGUUUCUUGGCACUUCUGCAUUGCUCUAGGUUACACAAACAGCUGCCUCAACCCAGUCCUUUAUGCAUUUCUGGAUGAAAACUUCAAACGAUGCUUCAGAGAGUUCUGUAUCCCAACCUCUUCCAACAUUGAGCAACAAAACUCCACUCGAAUUCGUCAGAACACUAGAGACCACCCCUCCACGGCCAAUACAGUGGAUAGAACUAAUCAUCAGCUAGAAAAUCUGGAAGCAGAAACUGCUCCGUUGCCCUAACAGGGUCUCAUGCCAUUCCGACCUUCACCAAGCUUAGAAGCCACCAUGUAUGUGGAAGCAGGUUGCUUCAAGAAUGUGUAGGAGGCUCUAAUUCUCUAGGAAAGUGCCUGCUUUUAGGUCAUCCAACCUCUUUCCUCUCUGGCCACUCUGCUCUGCACAUUAGAGGGACAGCCAAAAGUAAGUGGAGCAUUUGGAAGGAAAGGAAUAUACCACACCGAGGAGUCCAGUUUGUGCAAGACACCCAGUGGAACCAAAACCCAUCGUGGUAUGUGAAUUGAAGUCAUCAUAAAAGGUGACCCUUCUGUCUGUAAGAUUUUAUUUUCAAGCAAAUAUUUAUGACCUCAACAAAGAAGAACCAUCUUUUGUUAAGUUCACCGUAGUAACACAUAAAGUAAAUGCUACCUCUGAUCAAAGCACCUUGAAUGGAAGGUCCGAGUCUUUUUAGUGUUUUGCAAGGGAAUGAAUCCAUUAUUCUAUUUUAGACUUUUAACUUCACCUUAAAAUUAGCAUCUGGCUAAGGCAUCAUUUUCACCUCCAUUUCUUGGUUUUGUAUUGUUUAAAAAAAUAACAUCUCUUUCAUCUAGCUCCAUAAUUGCAAGGGAAGAGAUUAGCAUGAAAGGUAAUCUGAAACACAGUCAUGUGUCAGCUGUAGAAAGGUUGAUUCUCAUGCACUGCAAAUACUUCCAAAGAGUCAUCAUGGGGGAUUUUUCAUUCUUAGGCUUUCAGUGGUUUGUUCCUCAGUUUUAAAUGUGCAAUUUUCUUGCUCCUAUUUAAGUGUUCACAAAAGGUAAUAGUCAAUGAGCUCAUCACUUCAUCCAUGCAGGAAGUCAAGCAUUAAAAUGUACUCUUUAUUUCUCACUGGUUUCUCCAUACUGCAGGCUCCCCACAUAUUAUUUUCUUUUUUUAACUCAGCUCAGAAUCCUUAUGCCUUUUGAAUCAGUGUGAUAAAAUGACAGAUGUUUUUGUUGAUUGCCAGAACAGUUUAAACUUUUUUUAAACAAUAAAUCCAAUAAACAUAAUCUCAAGACAGACUCAUAUGACCAUACAGAAAAGUGUGUCAUCUAUUUUUCAAUCCUGUGUAGUUACUUGGAUGUGAAAUAUUAACAAUGGCCCAAAAAUAUUUUCCUGAAGAUUGUGUUUAUAUAAUGUCAUCACCAAUAUUUUGGUCUUUUUGAUCUCUGCUAAAUGUCAAGAUUUCCUUUGUAAAGUGUCGAUCUUCUAAGUAGUUUCUUUAAGACAAUUCUCCGCUUUAACUGAUUUUCUUUGUUGUGAAACACAGUAGAGAUUUGGCAAUCAACCAUUUUACUUGAUCUAGGUAGACAGCCAAGUCAGAUGGCCCAUGCCUAGAAGCUCUCCAUUUUGAACUUUUGUCAGCAUUGAUUAAAAGAAUCAAAUACCUUGUAGUUAUCUAUGAUGAUACAAGUAAAAAACUAGGCUGCUGACUUCUGAGUAUUCCUGAGCCUACAAUUGUAAAAUUGUAGACUCCAUUGUAAAAUUUGUAUUUUUUCAUCAAUCUGACAAGGCACAAAUAUGUGCCAGAUAUACAAAAGCAAUGUUUCUAGAAAACAGCUAUCAUGGAUCAGAAUAACUGAAUUUACUCUCAGAUCUAUUGGCUAUAGUUAUGUGGACUCAACCCACGUAUCCAGUAGAUGGGAAAAAACAAAAGCCAAAAUAAGUUUUUUAGUGUUUCCUUCUGAUGAAGUUUCAUGUUUGCUUGUAAUAAUCUCCAUUUCUCAAAUAUUAUGUUCCAUAAUAGACAUACAUUAUGUUUAAUUUUUUAUAUUUUCUGACAAAAGUAACUAAAACUAGGACCUUAAAAAGAUUUAGAAUGUUAAAUAAGUGUACUAGGGUGUAUAUAUUUACAUAUAUACACUACUAGAGCUUCCAAAAGUAAAAUGGAUAAUUCAAACAGAACACAAUGUAAUAUUUGUAUGUAAAUAACUGAGGAGGAAAAUCCAUGCUUUUCAUGGGCUAGGAUGGUUUCUCCCAAGAGAUGACAUAGUAUUGCUUUUGCUCAUCAGGCUGUUUCUCAGCAAUCAUUGUUUCUGCUUAAUACCAGCUCCUAGUACGAAUUAUCUGGCAUGUUGAGAGCAACUUUGUCUUCAAGUAGGACCUGAUCUAUCUUUUUCCACAAAUGUCAUGUGUGUGAACAAGUUUCUUCCAUGUCAUCUUUGAGACUCUACACAGAAUACACAAUAAAGGGAGUUAUUUUUAAAAUAAGACAUUCUAAAGUAAAUAAUAAAUAAGGUCAUUGUCAACGUUUUUCAUUCAAAACCAUUUUUUAACGUAAAUUUGCUAGAACCACCUUCCAAUUCCAAGGCAAGGAGAGACAUUACAACCCUGACUCAACUGGAUGGGCUAAGGUUUCUGAUAAAAUCUGAAGAUAAAGAAAAUGGAAUAUUCUGCUUUUUUCUUCCUUCUAAUUUCACCCUUGCCUAAGGAUGAGAUUUCUUCCCAGGUUGGUAUCCCAGAAAUGCAGACUGUAGCUAUGGGGCGGAAGCUUUGUUUCUUUACCUGAUCACUUGCUGUGGAAAUUCUAGCUUAUUGUGUUCCAAGUAGUUAGUGGUUUUUCUCCUUCAGUCUCCACUGUUAUUUUGCUCCUUCAUCCCUCUUUCCUUGCCAAUCAUUAGAAAGGAAAGAAGAGGAAAGAGACUCGCUGGAGCACUGGUGAGUCUCUAGGACCCUGCUAUCCUAUCCCAACAGGGCUGUCAGACGGAGAACUCCUAAUGUGGCCAUUUGAAACACUUCUCAACAUUGAAAUAGACAGUUGAAGUUUUAAAAUAACCUCUUCUAAGACACGGCUAUGAGUAGGUAAGAGAGCAUUCAUUCCCUUCAAUAAUAUGACUGUGUUGAUAAAACUGAUAACCAUUCACUUGCAAAUGUUAUUAUUGAAUAAGUCUCACUUAGCUCAUUUAAUAUUACCCAAAAGAUGCUAACAAAUUCUGUUUCCCACAUUGUCACAGCAUGCCCUUUACAUCUCAGGAUCCAGGCAAAAGUUGAAAUUCAGAAACAUAGAUAUGAAAUGUAAGAUACAAAGAAAACACCUCUGCAAAGAUUCCGACCACAUUUAUCAAAAAGUCCCCAAAGCAUUCAAAAUCUUUACUUAAGUCAAGUCUAUUUAUACGUUUAAAAGCUAAAAACAAGAUCUUUUUGGUAAUGCUUCAAUUAAAUGUUUUAUCUAAAUAUGUGGAAAUGAUAAGAUGCGUACUGCAUCUCUCAUAUAAUAAAGAUAAUCAGUUUUAUACAGACAUAUUCUCCAUCUACUGGCAAUUACCAAGAUAAGAUGGCACUAGAAAUUUCUCCAGCUUACGCCAUGAAUACUGCAGAAGCUGAUACUAUCCGUUGUGGUUUUACAAAUUCUAGAGGGUUCUAGCCAAAGCAACCUAAGAAUAGGACAUGGUAGCUUAAGUUUUUCAGCUUCUUAACUGGCCACACACACACAAGUUGUGUUUGUACAAUUCUUGAGGUCAAUCAGAACCAAAAAAUCUGUUGCUGGAAGAAAUAUUAUCCUCUUCAUAGAAAUAUCCACCAGCAGAAAAUUGGUUUCUCAAGGAAUCCCUACUGCCCUUGUAGAAACAUCAAGAUUCUUGCCUGGAUUCUCAACAUAAGUCUUUACUCACAGGCCUAUUGCUUGGUUUCAGAAGAGUGAGAACAUGAAAGUUCAUAAAUGCCUGGGCCACUGCAACUCUAACCACUGUGUUUCCCCCAGUUUGAUAUGGUUCAGGAUACAUAGUCAUAGAACAGGGCAUGCAGAUUGUAUUUAAGACCACUGCAAGUAAGGUCUAAGGCAAAAGUAAAUUAAUGAGUCCAACUCUGGGGCAUCCAUUUAAGAGCCAUUUAAUCCAUUUAAUUACAAAUAAUUUCAACCCAUAGUCAGUGUUCUUCACUGUCUUCAAAAAUAUAAAAAGUACAAGGAAUUGUGUACAUUACAAACUGCUCCAGAAACAAAACCAAAUGUGGAUAGCUUUGUGAGCUGCAGUGUGUGGCAAAUGUUCAACCUUUUGUUAUGCAAUAUCACCCAUAUCAAAUACCAUUCUUAAAGCAGUAGACAGAUGAGUCAAGUUCAAUUUAAUGCAAACAAUAUUACUGUGUUCUAAGCGCUUCUGUUACUCGAAAGGGGUCUGAUCCAGACCCCAAAAGAGGGUUCUUGGACCUCAUGCAAGAAAGAAUUCAGGAGUAAAGUGAAAGUGAAAUGGGUCAGGAUCAAUGGUCUCAUUGUCUAAGGUGUUAUCCGAGCUCGUUGUCUCACAACCAAGAAAAUUAAGGAGCAUGGACACAAAGGGUGAGGUUGGAGCAAAAGUUUAAUAAGCAAAAGAGGAAAGCUCUCUGCAGCAGAGACGGGAGCCCAAGUGGGUUGCUGUUUUUACAGCUGAAUCCAAAAGCUUUUAUAAGAAACUCCUCUCAUCUCUGCAGCUAUUUGAGUAACUUCUCUUAUCUGAAAAGCUGUCUGUACAACUGCCUCUAUCUAUGCAGCUAUGGGGUGUCUCUAGGCGAGCACAAAGCAUAGCUUCUCUUGUUGUAUAAUUGUGGGUUUGUUUUAAGUAAGCCACUUUCCUCCCUGCAAGUUCCCACGGAGCAGAAAAAAGGAGGAAACUUUUUCCUGGGAGCCCACUAAUCACACAGUGAACAAAAGGCUUCUAUGCUGGGCCUUACUUUCUAACAGUGCAGCAGUUAUAGUCUGAGUUUUCUCCAGGCUGCUCCAUUUUUGCCUGUAGCUAUGAUUUUUCAGGCAGCCUGCUUCUCCGAGGACUAGUCUUAGCUGUUUACCUAACUGAUUGGUCCUUUUCUUCUCCCUGAAAAGCAAGUUUAUUAAGAAAGCAAAGGAAUAAAGAAUGGCUACUCCAUAGGCAGCGUAGCCCCAAGGGCUGCUGGUUGGCUAUUUUUGUGGUUAUUUCUUGAUUAUAUGCUAAACAAGGGGUGGAUUAUUCAUGGGUUUUCUGGGAAAGGAGUGGGCAAUUCCCAGAACUGAGGGUUCUUCCCCUUUUAAGACCGCAUAGGGCAACUUCCUGACAUUGCCAUGGCAUUUGUAAACUGUCGUGGUACUGGUGGGAAUGUUUUUUAGCAUGCUAAUGCAAUAUAAUUAGUGUAUAAUGAGUAGUGAGGACAACCAGAGGUAACUUUCAUUGCCAUCUUGGUUUUAGUGGGGUUUGGCCGGCUUCUUUACCACAUCCUUUUAUCAGUAAGAUCUUCGUGACCUGUACCUUGUGCCAACCUCCUAUCUCUUCCUGUGACUUGGAAUGCCUAACCUCCUGGGAAUGCAGCCCAGUAGGUCUCAGCCUUAUUUUACCCAGCCUCUAUUCAAGAUGGAGUCGCUCUGGUUCAAACACCUCUGACACUUGAAUUACAAAUAUAAGGACCAUUGACACUGAGAUUUUAAGGGAGGAAAAACAGAUUGACAGUGGACUAAAGGUACUUUUGUAGCAAGGUACUUUCCACACAAUAUUGAAUAAAUGCAGUGUAUACAUUUUUAAAGGAAUUUUAAGAGCUCGGAAAUCAUUAAAAUUAAGUUUAUCAAUUUUUGAAAGCAUCUUCUGACUCAAAUAUAUGAAAAGAUUAUUCUAGACCUUAGGCAGAUAUUCAGAGAAAGAUCAGUUUUCUAUGGGUUUUUUCCAUCAUGCAUUUUAUACAAAUUUAAUAUACUUUUUCAACUCACUUUGCAUUUCCUGUUACCUUGUACUGAGAACUUCAUUAAAACCUGCACUUGAAAUUGCACUUAAACUUUACAAAAUCACAGAAGAAGUUGUUUUCCAUAGGUGUGGGGUGGGAUGUUAGAGCUCUAGACAUUAAUUCCUAGGAAUCGCAUACCUACGGAAAACAGUCCUCUGACCUCCUGUGACACAUGGGGUGAGCCCUUCCUUUUUGUCUCAAUCUCAAAAAACAGUAAGUCUUUAAUCCAUUUGCAUCAAAAAGUACUUCAUAUGCUCGAAACUAAAGUAAAACUUUAUUGAAAUACAUUAAUAUGCUCCUGGAACAUACUACUGGGUCUCAGACAGUGCAGAAGCUUUAUUGUUUAUUUGGGAAGAGCAAGGUAAGAAUCAAGUAGAAAUGAUAAAGGGCAAGGAAAAAAGAUGAAAGCUUACUCAUAUUAACCAUUCUACCAUUGGAAUUAUUUGCCAACACACCUUGCUGCUACUUAGAGAAAGUAGUUCACCUCACUACCUUUUAUCCAAAGAAAUUAUCUCUAAAAGCACUCAGACAUUUUGUAGAGCAAGUAGCAAUCUAUUCAAAGUUGUAAAGGUUCUGUAGAAUCUCUCAGACCAGGUACAGGACCUACCAAAGGCCACAGCCAAGCACAAGCAGCUACAUUAGACAGUUUUACAGCUCUGUAUUUCAGGAAAACUUCUGUCCUGUGGGAGCAAUACAAAACUAUACCAGUUUUUUGUUAGUGUAAAAAUUGCCCAAUAUUAACCAGAGCAGCCCAAAAUAUUUCAGGGUAAGAAUAGAUAUAUUUAUAUUUUUCAGAUGAUAUAUCUUCAUUUUCGAUUUUGAAAGAACAGUAAUACUAAUUAUAUCCCAUGUAAGGGGCUACUGACAAUUUUGAUGGUACCUGAAUUUGCCUCUAUCAUGCAUCUCAAUGAUUUGUUGUCAUCCAAAGCUAUUUCAUGAAUCAAAUAUCGUUUUCUACCUGCCCCACAACUGUGUACAUAAAACCUAAACCUCUGAAGCAAUAAACCUCUUCCAUUACACAGGUUUAGAUUCAGAGUUUUCUUGCUUAAGUUCCAACUAAAAGUAUUACAUUCUUAGCAUAAGUAUACUCAUAAAGAAAAAUAAGUAUUUGUUUUAGGUUUUAGAGAGAGAGCACAGAGUCCCUUUGAGACAGUGGGGAAAAUUCAUCUUCAUAUUGUCACAUGCACUGUAAUAGGAAUGUUUAGCAAAAAAAACCUUCCAGAGAAAGGUGGUUUCCAAUAUUACCUACAACUUCCUUUGCAAUUUGAUUUUUGAAAGGACCUAAAAGUUGAAAACAGGCUAUCACAUCCCAUUUGCUUUAAAGUCUCUUAAACUUACGCUCUUUCGCUUCAAAUGCAUAAAUGUUUUAUUUAAGUUUGCAUUGCCCACUAAGGCUAGACAUUUUUUUUUUUUUUUUUUUUUUUUUUUUUUUGAGACAGAGUCUCGCUCUGUCGCCCAGGCUGGAGUACAGUGGCGGGAUCUCGGCUCACUGCAAGCUCCGCCUCCCGGGUUCACGCCAUUCUCCUGCCUCAGCCUCCCAAGUAGCUGGGACUACAGGCGCCCGCCACUACGCCCGGCUAAUUUUUUGUAUUUUUAGUAGAGACGGGGUUUCACCGUUUUAGCCGGGAUGAUCUCGAUCUCCUGACCUCGUGAUCCGCCCGCCUCGGCCUCCCAAAGUGCUGGGAUUACAGGCGUGAGCCACCGCGCCCGGCCCGGCUAGACAUUUUUUGAUAAAUUCACAGGGUUACAAAAUACCAAACGGAAAUGAGAUAAGUGGUAUAAACCACAGAAGAUAUAGGAGAAGAGAAAAAAAAAAGAGGAAAUAAAGAAGACAACUCUUUUCCUAAGAGUCUGGGUAAAAUUGAACAUAGCCAUAUUCACUGAACAACAUGAGUGAGCUUCAUUAAUUUAAGCACAGCAAAACUGCUUUAAUUAACAAGACCAGAGAGAAGGGAGAGGAGACUACAUUUGUGUGACCUAAUGGUUGUGAUUUCACUGUCCAAGAGGACAAAGACAAAGAAAUUCUGGGAAGGAGAACAACAAUUAUAUUCCCCCAUUUCAAGAAGGGCAGAAGUGUCCCAACACUACCCAAUAUUUGCAAAAUUCAAAUGUCUCAUAGGCUCUUCUUCCCUGGUUCCCUCAGGAGCUGGGUUUCUGGGUUGCAGAAGUGCUUUUCAUAUUCUGUAUCUGGUUGUGGUGGCAAUGUCACCACCCUACACUGCUGUGACACCGAAACAACCAAGCCUAGAAUCAGCUGGUGCCUCUUUUCAUCUGCAGGGUAGAUUUGGCUUCCAUGGUUGUUCACUGCUCUGUGUUAGGAAGGCUCAGUGACAGGUGUACAGCCUUCAGUAAUGCCUCAAAGGUUCUCCAAGCAGAGGUAAACAUGUGGGUCCUGCUGGUGACAUAUUAGACUUCUUACUUUCCCCAAAUAAAAAAGUGCCUGCUGGGCGCGGUGGCUCACGCCUGUAAUUCCAGCACUUUGGGAGGCCGAGGCGGGCGGAACACAAGGUCAGGAGAUCAAGACCAUCCUGGCCAAUAUGGUAAAACCCCAUCUCUACUAAAAAUACAAAAUUAGGAAGGCGUGGUGGUGCACGCCUGUAAUCCCAGCUAGUCGGGAGGCUGAGGCAGGAGAAUUGCUUGAACUGGGGAGGCGGAAGUUGCAGUGAGCCAAGAUCGCAGCAUUGCACUCCAGCCUGGGCAACAGAAUGAGAUUGUCUCAAAAAAAAAAAAAAGUGCCACAUGCCAUGCUAUGUGCCCAAAGUUUCCUUCACACAACACAGCCUUGAGAUGCAGUAUUAAAUUCUACACUUUUCCUACCAUAGUGAUACAUGUGGCUUUUCUUUGCUGUGUUCUGAGAUGUCAUGCUUUGAAAUCAGUGGCCAUUAUCAUCUAAGGAUUCCGCCAGAGACUUCCAAAAGAAGAGGUCUCAUUUAUAAAGUGAAUUUGAAUAAAAUGACCAGUUAGGUGUUUUCAGAAACACCUAUGCCCUACUUGCCUACUCUUCAAGGGUUUAGGGGCUUAGGGGGAGGUUUUGUUUGGGUUUUUUGUUGCUGUUGCUUGUUUAUUUGUUUGUUGUGUUUAAGACGUUUUACUUGUCCCUGAAAUGUUUGUCAUCACACAGAUACACGCUCAGGAUAAGAACUACCAGACUAGAUUAGGAGGUCCACACCACCAAUUGAGAUGUACCUGUGCUCAUGACUUGACAUUGUGGUGGGCCGGCUACAACCCUCCCCACCCCUCGCUUUCACUAAAUAACAACUCUCUUCUCUCCAUCAUUUUGACUUAGAGCCAGUCAGAAUUCAAUCUCCAAUAUCCUGACUAGCACAAGAAAUCCAUAGGUUGAUUCUUGUUCUCCUGCAUCUCUGCAGGUGGCAAACCUGAUUCCUAAUGCCUGUUCCUGCCUCUGCAGGGGUUCAUUCAGAAAACAGGAAAAUAACAAAGGCUUCCUGUAAUUCUCUUUGGCUGUAAUACAAUUUGUUCCCGUCUGCCCCCAGGCUCACCCAGUGCUCUGUCUCAGUGGUAAGCUGUAACUGAUCACUGCUGUAUUAACUCAAAACUCAUUUGCUUUAUGGAAAUUCAUGGCCCUUAUUUCUCAAGGGACCAGAGAAAACCAAUAGGCCUACUCCCCAGCUGAGUACUUUCCAUGCAAGCUACCGCAUCUGUAUAAAUUAGGUUCAAAUAACAGAGUAUUUCCAGGAUUUAUAAAUUCAGUAUUACAAAUAGUAAUCUGGCAAGUGUUCUCAGGAUCCCCUUGCUACCUGUAAUUCAAUCAUAUAACUUCUGAAUGGGCUGGGGGAAAAUAACAAUAAGAAAAACUGGUGUUUACCUGAAGAUCUGCCCAGUGAUUUGUGUGUUUUCUUAAUAAACUUUACCCACUUAUUAAAAGAAUAAAAUGAAGGUGGAGUUAAUUCUGACUACGGGAUUCCUUUUUCACUUUUAUAAUGAACUCCUUCCUUCUAACUAAAUCUUAUCAUAAGCAAAUCUAUGCACCAAAUUAUUUAGUACAAUUCCUAAUAACAGCUGAAGGACCAUUUAUUUGAAGCAAUGUUCACCAUAGCAAAAUUCCAGUGAAGUCUAAGAACUGGGACAGUCCGUUGAGGAUCCUUGUGCCAGGAUGUAUGUUGCCCCAUGAAUGUGCACAUGCAUAUUAAAAUAUGGGCACCUCUUUUAAUUCUUUUUUUUCUCAUAAUAAGUUUGAAACUCACAGUAGGAAAUUGAGAGAUCAAUUUGGUUACUGUUUUAUCAUUGAUCCUGAAGACAGUUGAAGCAAUCAUACUGGUUGUUCUCGAACUAGCUGGUUUCCCAGAGACAGCUGGAGACUGAGCACAUAAAGACAUCAUUGAGGAAAAAGGCUACCUUGUACCUCAUGGAGAGCUGAAGGUCUGAUAAAUGGGAACUGCCAGGUAAUAGCUAUGCUAUUUCUGACAUAAAUUUAAAAACUAGUAUUGUUUCUUCUAGCUCUGUUUUUGCAUAGUGCACAGAGAUCUUUGUAAAAAACAGGAAAUUAAUGUUAAAUUGGAUCUAUAAACAUAAGUCAAUUUGGCUCUAUUAUGUCAAAAGAGAAUAGGAGUUUUAACUUAUAUCUGUGUUUUAUUAAUAUUUUGAAGUAUAGGAACCUCAUGGUGUAGCAGGAUGAGCCACAGACAAAACCUCUCAGACACCGAGUUGUAGAAGGAAGGGCUUUAUUCAGCUGGGAGCAUCGACCAGCUACUGUCUCAAAAUCCAAGCUCCCUGAGUACACAAUUUCUGUCCCUUUUAAGGGCUCACAACACUAGAUUUCACAUGAAAGGGUCGUGAUUGAUUUGAGCAAGCAAGGGGUAUGUGACAGGGGCUGCAUGCACCGGUGGUCUGGGAGGAACAGAACAGGACAGGGAGUUCUUCUAUACAAUAGAGAACAGAACAAUGUUCUUCUAUACAAUGUAAGGAAUCUAUGAAUAACAUCGGCUUCUAAAUCAUAAGUUGAUUUUUAACUACUGGGUUUAGGCCAGGCGGGCCCAGGCCUGGUUUCGGGCCUGGCGCUGAGCUGCCUGUAUUUGGUUUUACUUCCUUGUUGUUUUUACUGAAUAUGAAACAAUAUAAAACAAUGUGAGAGGGUCUUUCUCUCCUCUCAAUGUCAACAUCAUAUAUGAUUGGAGACUUCCACAUAAUUGAGUUUUAGUGCCCACUGUUACAGAAAAUCAUAAUGGAAAAACUAAAAUGUCAAUAAUAAUUUCAGAUGUGUAUUUUAGUUCUCAUAAGAACAUCUACAUUCAUUUGAAAAAUAGUUCUAUAUCUAUUCUUGAAACAUAUUUCUUUAGUUCAAGGUCUGAUGAGCUCCCAGACUGUUGGGGAUUGCUCUACAGCUGCUCAAGCUUUUGAAGACUCCUGUGAUUUUUUUAAAUGGCUGGUUUGGUUGAAGUUUCUCUUAUCAGUCAGGCACUUUGCAUUUUAAGCGUACUUUACCACCGACACCCUCCCCCCCCAGCACACACACACACACACACACACACACACACACAACAUAGUGAAAUGGACCCGUGGGAAUUAUAUGAUAGUUGUAAUCAAAAUAAAAUGCAAUCAAUACUAAAAUACAAUUUACCAAAGGCUUACCUCCUUAUUUGAAACUCCAGCAUCAAUAAUUUACUUGCACUCUUGUUAUUUACAUUUGUACUCUGGAAGUAAACUUAAAAUGAAAAUUAGAAUUUGCUUUCAAUUAUACUAUCUCUAUCUAAAUCUUAAUUUGAAAUUUAAAUUAUUUUGUCUCUACCCAAACCAUCGAUUUCAUGGAAAUGUUUAAAUUUUCUUUUUUUUUUUUUUUUUUGAUGGAGUCUCACUCUGUCGCCCAGGCUGGAGUGCAGUGGCUCAAUCUUGGCUCACUGCAACCUCUGCCUCCCGGGUUCACACCAUUCUCCUGCUUCAGCCUCCUGAGUAGCUGGGACUACAGGUGCCCGCCACAACACCUGGCUAAUUUUUUGUAUUUUUAGUAGAGAUGGGGUUUCACCACGUUAGCCAGGAUGGUUUCGAUCUCCUGACCUCGUGAUCUGCCUGCCUCGGCCUCCCAAAGUGUUGGGAUUACAGGUGUGAGCCACUGCGCCUGGCCAGAAAUGUUUAAAAUUUCAUAAAUCUUGAAUCCAUAAAAUUCAAUGCUACCAUUUAUAAUUUAAUACUCCUACCAUAAAAAUUUCUGUGUUAGGCAUAGCUAUAUGAAUAUUUGCCUAUAAAUCCCCAUCAAUUUAAUAGGAAUUAAGUUAGAAAUACUAGUAUAUAUAUUCCCUUUAUAUACUAAUUGUAUAUCCAUAUAAAAGCAUUAGUACCAUUAUAUGAAAGUAUAUAUGCCAUUCCAUAAAAAUAUAUCUACCAAUAUAAAUAGAAUAUAUAAAGGGAAUAUAUAUAUACCAAUAUAAAUGGGAAUUUAUAUUGGCACAUACAUUUCCAUUAUUUUAAUGGGAAUUAAAGAAAAAAUGCCUGUUUUCACUAAGUCAUCCUUCCCCUGGCAAUACAUUUCCUGAACUUUUACAUACUUAAAUAGCCAGUUAUGAAAAUGUAAAACAAUGAGUGAUCUUGUUGUUUUCAUUUUAUUAUGUUAUAUGAAAAAAAGAAACCUUGUAAGUGCAGAUUUAUUUUAAAAAAUUGAAAAACUACUCUGUCAAACAUAGCAAAUAGGAAAGUUAAAAAAAAGUAAGUCUAAAGAUUAGGUGCUCUGUCACUUGUCAUUACAUUUUUUUAUAACAUUAAUGACACAUUUUUUGCUAUCCAAAUAUAAUUUCCACUAGAAAAGAAAAGAUGUCCUCCAUGUUUUAAAUUGCAUUUGAAAUUCAGGUAACUAAUAACCCUUGGUUUUAAAAGAUACAUAUAAUGUUUCCGUAGGAAAAAAAUCAAAAUAUUGUAAAGAAUCUGAGUAAAUGAGAGCCUCUCAUGGUUGAUUAAGUUCAGACAUUUUAAACAGACUCCUGCCCACAAACUAUUUUUCCUCUCCAGGAAUAAGAAUGGCAACUGAAUUGUUCCUUCUUUAUUCUAUAGCUUUAAGUCAAACCUAACAUAAGCAAUCAACCCUUCCACCCAUUGUCCUCUUUCUAGCUGCUUAUAUUCCUGAGUCUGAAAGAAGGGCAGAAUUAAUUCGUUUCCUUGACAGUGUUGGGGGUGAAAUAAAAGAUAGACCCCUGCUGCUCUGCACGUAGAUUCAGUUUGUAUGCCAGGGUGACAUUUUAAUUUACAGUAGUCCAGACACCUAAACAGGACAUAGAAAUGUCAACUGGUCAUAUUAAAAUAAAAAAGUAUAGAAUAGUUUCUGUUUUACGGAUUUUGUAUCCAAGUAAAUGAAAACACAAUCACCUUUCAAAACAUGGUAUGAAAUCCACAGUUGUAACAGUGAGCACAACAUGCUUUCUGUGUGUGUUUUUAAGCUCUUUCCCCACAUCUGCUUUUCAAAAAUAUUUGCCUGGAAACCUGUAUUUCGCCUAUAGAGACAAAUACAUAUAUUGUUUGUUGUGAUAAUGCACAAAAAGGAAUGUUAAAAAAAAACACACAACAUUGUUUUCCUUUUGAUGGUCUGGGAGUUUUUCUAUAAGUUUUUGGUUUUUUUUUUUUUUUCUCUUCAUUAGUGUGUUAGUUCCAUCAUCAUGUCUGUUUACUAUUGAAAAAUAAAUAUCUUCAUUUAAAGUAGAGACAAAGCUACUAUUUCACAUUUCCAGGUAGGACAGGAUGAUCAGAUGCAGCUUUCAAAAGAACUACCUGCUAAAUCAUAAUGGUCUCAUGUGCAGAUCAAAAUGUCAACUAGUAUAUCAAACAGUGAGCAAUUCACUAAAUUAUUUUUACAUUACUCCUAUUUGACUGUUUCAGAUAGUUGUAUAUAAAAAAUAUAAAUUUUUGCAUUGUAUUGUUCUUGAUGUACCAGCAUACAUAAACAUAUUAGGCUGUAUUGUAAGUUUCCUGCAUGUAAUAUGUAAUGUGUAAUUAUAUGUGAUAAAUAAAACCUAAAACUGAUACAAA